AUCGCGGCUAGAGAGAUGUCGCUGCUGCGGUCGCUGCGCGUGUUUCUGGUCGCGCGGACCGGGAGCUACCCGGCUGGGUCUCUUCUGCGUCAGUCGCCCCAGCCAAGGCACACAUUUUAUGCUGGGCCCCGUCUGUCUGCCUCGGCCUCCAGCAAGGAGCUCCUCAUGAAGCUGCGGCGGAAAACAGGCUACUCCUUUGUAAAUUGCAAGAAAGCUCUGGAGACUUGUGGCGGGGACCUCAAACAGGCAGAGAUCUGGCUCCACAAGGAGGCCCAGAAGGAGGGCUGGAGCAAAGCUGCCAAGCUCCAAGGGAGGAAGACCAAAGAAGGCCUGAUUGGGCUGUUGCAGGAAGGAAACACAACUGUAUUAGUAGAGGUAAACUGUGAGACAGAUUUUGUUUCUAGAAAUUUAAAAUUUCAACUGUUGGUCCAGCAAGUAGCCCUUGGAACCAUGAUGCAUUGUCAGACCCUAAAGGAUCAACCCUCUGCAUACAGUAAAGUGCAGUGGCUCACGCCUGUAAACCUAGCACUUUGGGAGGCUGAAGCAGGUGGAUCACUUGAGGGUUUCUUGAAUUCCUCUGAGCUUUCUGGACUUCCAGCUGGGCCUGACAGAGAAGGCUCACUCAAGGAUCAGUUGGCUUUAGCAAUUGGAAAACUGGGAGAAAACAUGAUUCUUAAACGAGCUGCAUGGGUGAAGGUGCCAUCUGGGUUCUACGUUGGCUCUUAUGUCCACGGAGCAAUGCAGAGUCCCUCACUUCACAAGCUGGUGCUGGGGAAGUAUGGGGCCCUGGUCAUCUGUGAGACGUCUGAACAGAAAACAAACCUUGAAGACGUUGGCCGCCGCCUUGGGCAGCAUGUGGUGGGCAUGGCCCCCCUCUCUGUUGGCUCCCUGGACGAUGAGCCUGGGGGAGAGGCAGAGACUAAGAUGCUGUCCCAGCCGUAUUUGCUGGAUCCCUCCAUUACCUUGGGGCAGUAUGUGCAGCCUCAGGGGGUGUCGGUAGUAGACUUUGUGCGGUUUGAAUGUGGAGAAGGUGAAGAGGCAGCAGAAACUGAAUAGGUUCCAGAGACUUUUGGCCCAGGAGGAAUAUUUACUUUUAGCUCUGGACAUCAUUACAAAAAGGAAUAUUUCCCAAACCUCUUCAGACCGAGAAUGCAUGGGUAAAAUUAUUAAAUAGUUGUAUAAUAAAAAUAAUUUUUUCCUUGUUUGCGUAAUACUGGAUUUAGCUUUUCUGUGCCUUUCAAAAACAACAGGUGGGCCUUAUUGACGUGAUAGUGUCGUGGAGAACAGGCAUCAACAAUACUGCUGCUCCCUUCAACAUAGAUUUAUUAUGGUAUUUCUGAAAUUUCUAACUUAUAUGUUCUGUCUUACACCUUUUAUGACAUAGAACUCUUUUGUUCUGUUUUUGCUUUGCGACACUGUGAACCGUGCUUCUGCCUCGGAACCUCCCUAGUUAUAUUACUUGUGCCACAUGGAUUUCUUUAGGAUUAUUGAUUCAAACCUAGAGUUGUCUGGAAAAUGUGGGUUCUCUUCUUUGUGAUUGUCUGUAGUAUGCUUUGAAGGUGCUCUGCAGUGGUAGACACACUGGUUCUGGCCUCAUUUAAUGAAAUUAAUAACACAUGCCCCUAUUUCUCUUUUGGAUGAUGUGUGGGUGGGUGGGUACUGAGGUUUCCUGGCCAGCUGUAAGGCAGAUUUUGACAUUCUUGUGCCAGAAACAGAAAUUAGAGUAGUCCAGUUACCCAGAGAGCUCACUUAACAUUGCCUCUUUACUUCCCCAGUACUGAAACAUUUCUUCAAGUAUAACAUAAAAUUACCGUAACAAGCAGACCCAGAAUACUGAAAAUAACUCCAUUUGUUCAUUAUAGGUAUCUUUAUUUGAAAAGUGAAAAAUGCUUUGACACAUUACAGAUCUGGGUAUUUGGAUUUUGCCUAUGGAGUGCAUAUAUGAUUUCAAUGAUUUACAGGCUAAAUAGAUUUUAGAAAUAAUCAUCUUAAAAUUGAAAACAAAGGUAGGUCCUGGUAUAAUAUUAAACAUAAAGUUAUUAAACAUUUUAAGCAUUGUU